GUUACUCCCCCUGCUGAAGCUGAAGGUUGGUGGAGUGAUGGAGCGUGGGGAUGGUAAAGGAGGAGUAAGUAGCUUUCCACAGACUCCCAGGUCUCUGGCCCCUUCCCAGCUUCUUGGGAAAUUGAGAGCCCUCCAGGCAGACAGAGAACAGAACUAGAAGGAGGGGUGGUGCUUAGUCUUAAAUAGCUCAAGGAGGCAGGUUGGAGUGUGAAACUGCUGUUCUUGGCAACCCAGAAGGCUACUCUGCCUGGGGGAAGGCUGGAAACUCACCUGCUUGUUUUUAUUUUUCCGAGAAGAUCUGUGCUGUCUCCUUGAGCUUAUAAAAACAGAGGAAGCACAGGGUGGCCUCCUCGCAAAGUCAAGGCUAGAAGACUCCCUUCUCCUGUUCUCUUUUCCACUCAUGCCCUCCCUUAUUUAAAAAAAAAAAAAAAAAGAAAGAAAAGAAAAAAAAAAGAACUCAUUUCCUUUCCUAACCUAGGUAGGCAGAAAUCUAUUAGCAGAGUGCGCAUGGGCAGGGCCUGACAGGUGUGUUGUGUCAAGAAAGACAGGUGCAAAUUUCCUCUGUGUCUGUGUGUGUCUGUACAGCUCUAGACCACAAUGCUUGCUCGAGGGUUGGAGAGGUUUAUGAAUUUAUGGUUGUCCUGGUUAAUAGGAUUGUCUGGGCUAAUGGGAAUUGGGCUGUUGUUCUUUUGAGCCCUGCCAUGUGAGUUCUUGGGGUGGGGGGUGGGGGCAAGUUGGUAUGUGUUUGUUUAUUUUUCUUAAGGAUAUUGGCAGUCUACUGCUGAGGCUGUGUCCCAGGCUUCUGUCUGCCAGUCAGCCCAAAGCACCCCCACUUUAGGCAGCAGGUGGAGGGAGACUGACUUUUCCUUUGCUUCCUACCAGUUUAUGCCUAUCUCCCAGGUCUGUGCUUGGCAGAGAGAGAGAGAGAGAGAGAGAACUGUCGUGUGUGUGUGUGUGUGUGUGUGUGUGUGUGUGUGUGUGUGUUUGUGUGUGUGUGGUGUAUGCUUUGGAUAGCAAUGAGUGGUGUGUAACUGCCAAGAAUUCCAAAGUCAGUUUGAAAGUGUUACUGUUGUUAAAGCUUAUCUUUUUAAGCAUGCUUUCUCCUUGCCCAGAAAGAAUAGGUAUGUACAUAAACUCUUUCAAGUCAUAUGUUAAAUAAUCUCAUAAAGUAGAAUGAGCCUGUCAUUGUCCCAGACAUGUGCCAAAUGUCCUAGAUAUGAAUUUGAUGGAGAAAGAAAAUCUCAAGUACAUGAGAAGGGUCCCGGGAUUCUUGAGCUGUGCCCAGCUGACGAGCUUUUGAAGAUGGCACAAUAACCGUCCAGUGAUGCCUGACCAUGACAGCACAGCCCUCUUAAGCCGGCAAACCAAGAGGAGAAGAGUUGACAUUGGAGUGAAAAGGACGGUAGGGACAGCAUCUGCAUUUUUUGCUAAGGCAAGAGCAACGUUUUUUAGUGCCAUGAAUCCCCAAGGUUCUGAGCAGGAUGUUGAGUAUUCAGUGGUGCAGCAUGCAGAUGGGGAAAAGUCAAAUGUACUCCGCAAGCUGCUGAAGAGGGCGAACUCGUAUGAAGAUGCCAUGAUGCCUUUUCCAGGAGCAACCAUAAUUUCCCAGCUGUUGAAAAAUAACAUGAACAAAAAUGGUGGCACGGAGCCCAGUUUCCAAGCCAGCGGUCUCUCUAGUACAGGCUCCGAAGUACAUCAGGAGGAUAUAUGCAGCAACUCUUCAAGAGACAGCCCCCCAGAGUGUCUUUCCCCUUUUGGCAGGCCUACUAUGAGCCAGUUUGAUAUGGAUCGCUUAUGUGAUGAGCACCUGAGAGCAAAGCGCGCCCGGGUUGAGAAUAUAAUUCGGGGUAUGAGCCAUUCCCCCAGUGUGGCAUUAAGGGGCAAUGAAAAUGAAAGAGAGAUGGCCCCGCAGUCUGUGAGUCCCCGAGAAAGUUACAGAGAAAACAAACGCAAGCAAAAGCUUCCCCAGCAGCAGCAACAGAGUUUCCAGCAGCUGGUUUCAGCCCGAAAAGAACAGAAGCGAGAGGAGCGCCGACAGCUGAAACAGCAGCUGGAGGACAUGCAGAAACAGCUGCGCCAGCUGCAGGAAAAGUUCUACCAAAUCUAUGACAGCACUGAUUCGGAAAAUGAUGAAGAUGGUAACCUGUCUGAAGACAGCAUGCGCUCGGAGAUCCUGGAUGCCAGGGCCCAGGACUCUGUCGGAAGGUCAGAUAAUGAGAUGUGCGAGCUAGACCCAGGACAGUUUAUUGACCGAGCUCGAGCCCUGAUCAGAGAGCAGGAAAUGGCUGAAAACAAGCCGAAGCGAGAAGGCAACAACAAAGAAAGAGACCAUGGGCCAAACUCCUUACAACCGGAAGGCAAACAUUUGGCUGAGACCUUGAAACAGGAACUGAACACUGCCAUGUCGCAAGUUGUGGACACUGUGGUCAAAGUCUUUUCGGCCAAGCCCUCCCGCCAGGUUCCUCAGGUCUUCCCACCUCUCCAGAUCCCCCAGGCCAGAUUUGCAGUCAAUGGGGAAAACCACAAUUUCCACACCGCCAACCAGCGCCUGCAGUGCUUUGGCGACGUCAUCAUUCCGAACCCCCUGGACACCUUUGGCAAUGUGCAGAUGGCCAGUUCCACUGACCAGACAGAAGCACUGCCCCUGGUUGUCCGCAAAAACUCCUCUGACCAGUCUGCCUCCGGCCCUGCCGCUGGCGGCCACCACCAGCCCCUGCACCAGUCGCCUCUCUCUGCCACCACGGGCUUCACCACGUCCACCUUCCGCCACCCCUUCCCCCUUCCCUUGAUGGCCUAUCCAUUUCAGAGCCCAUUAGGUGCUCCCUCCGGCUCCUUCUCUGGAAAAGACAGAGCCUCUCCUGAAUCCUUAGACUUAACUAGGGAUACCACGAGUCUGAGGACCAAGAUGUCAUCUCACCACCUGAGCCACCACCCUUGUUCACCAGCACACCCGCCCAGCACCGCCGAAGGGCUCUCCUUGUCGCUCAUAAAGUCCGAGUGCGGCGAUCUUCAAGAUAUGUCUGAAAUAUCACCUUAUUCGGGAAGUGCAAUGCAGGAAGGAUUGUCACCCAAUCACUUGAAAAAAGCAAAGCUCAUGUUUUUUUAUACCCGUUAUCCCAGCUCCAAUAUGCUGAAGACCUACUUCUCCGACGUAAAGUUCAACAGAUGCAUUACCUCUCAGCUCAUCAAGUGGUUUAGCAAUUUCCGUGAGUUUUACUACAUUCAGAUGGAGAAGUACGCACGUCAAGCCAUCAACGAUGGGGUCACCAGUACUGAAGAGCUGUCUAUAACCAGAGACUGUGAGCUGUACAGGGCUCUGAACAUGCACUACAAUAAAGCAAAUGACUUUGAGCAGGUUCCAGAGAGAUUCCUGGAAGUUGCUCAGAUCACAUUACGGGAGUUUUUCAAUGCCAUUAUCGCAGGCAAAGAUGUUGAUCCUUCCUGGAAGAAGGCCAUAUACAAGGUCAUCUGCAAGCUGGAUAGUGAAGUCCCUGAGAUUUUCAAAUCCCCGAACUGCCUACAAGAGCUGCUUCAUGAGUAGAAAUUUCAACAACUCUUUUUGAAUGUAUGAAGAGUAGCAGUCCCCUUUGGAUGUCCAAGUUAUAUGUGUCUAGAUUUUGAUUUCAUAUAUAUGUGUAUGGGAGGCAUGGAUAUGUUAUGAAAUCAGCUGGUAAUUCCUCCUCAUCACGUUUCUCUCAUUUUCUUUUGUUUUCCAUUGCAAGGGGAUGGUUGUUUUCUUUCUGCCUUUAGUUUGCUUUUGCCCAAGGCCCUUAACAUUUGGACACUUAAAAUAGGGUUAAUUUUCAGGGAAAAAGAAUGUUGGCGUGUGUAAAGUCUCUAUUAGCAAUGAAGGGAAUUUGUUAACGAUGCAUCCACUUGAUUGAUGACUUAUUGCAAAUGGCGGUUGGCUGAGGAAAACCCAUGACACAGCACAACUCUACAGACAGUGAUGUGUCUCUUGUUUCUACUGCUAAGAAGGUCUGAAAAUUUAAUGAAACCACUUCAUACAUUUAAGUAUUUUGUUUGGUUUGAACUCAAUCAGUAGCUUUUCCUUACAUGUUUAAAAAUAAUUCCAAUGACAGAUGAGCAGCUCACUUUUCCAAAGUACCCCAAAAGGCCAAAUUAAAAAAGAAAAAUAAUCACUCUCAAGCCUUGUCUAAGAAAAGAGGCAAACUCUGAAAGUCGUACCAGUUUCUUCUGGAGGCAAAGCAAUUUUGCACAAAACCAGCUCUCUCAAGAUGAGACUAGAAAUUCAUACCUGGUCUUGUAGCCACCUCUCUAAACUUGAAAAUAGGUUCUUCUUCAUAAGUGAGCUUACAUCAUUCUUCAUAAAGAAAAAUCCUAUAACUUGUUAUCAUUUUUGCUUCAGAUACUAAAAGGCACUAAGUUUCCAAUUUACGCUGCUCAACUUUGUUUAUAUGCUUAAAAGGAUUCUGUUUACUUAACAAUUUUUUCCCCUAAAAUACUAUUUUCUGAAUACUUCCUUCCAGUAAGGAAUAAAGGAAAGCCCAACUUGGCCAUAAAAUUCUUGCCUACACUAGAAGUUUGUUGACAGCCAUUAGCUGACUUGAUCGUCAUCUCCUAAGAGGAACACAUAUAUUUUCACAAGCAAUUCCACACUAUCCUGAUGGGUAUGCAAAGUGGUGACAGUCUAACUCAGUGUUUCUUCAUUUUAGGUAUAACAUUUUAAAGCAAUUGAUAAUGCCUCUUCCAAUUCAGAAGCUAGUAUUGACCAAAAUGUGAGAAGAGUGUAUAGCAUAGGAAAAUUUGGGGUUAACCCAAAAGACACAAUUCCAGCACACAUAAGAAAGCUAGCUGCUAUUUUAUGCUUUCUUCCAUGGUUCUCCUCUUUUUUCCCUUUUAUUUUUCCCUGUUUUUCAAUGAUGUACAGUGUUCCCUACUUGCAUUGAAAAAACUCGUAUGGCAUUCACACUUUUUUUCUUAGGUGGGUUUUUGUGUCCAGAUGCAGUAAGAAUUCAUUGUUCAUCCUAAAACUGUUUUCCAGACCCUUCCUUCCCCUUAGGUAAUUUGAUAUACACCUCCUAAAAUGACACAGUAACAAAUCUGGUAUUUAGAACAUAUAGAACAUAAAUGCCAUUUUUUAAUUCAACUUUAAUAAGAAUUACAUUUGACUUUGGAGAAUACAGGUCUUGACCCAUGUGACUGACUAGCUGACCCGAUCGCUGUAAUUUAACGUCAUUUAUAAAUUCUGCUGAUGGACAGGAAUGUAUGAACUCAAUUAUUGUCAGCACAAAGCCUUAAAACCUGCUGACUUUAAAUUAAAUGGUGCAGUCCUAUGAUGCCCUGCACCAUCCAGGGGACUAACAGGGCCUCGCAGUGUAGACAGAGGGUGCAGCCACACGGGCGGGGGCACCAGCCACCUCACUCUGCACCCGCGGCCUCACACAUCUCCCAGCUCACACUCUACUAAUGCACAGAGUCAUUAGAUCCAAUUUGUUAUUUUUCUCACUUGCUUUAAAAAAAAGCAGUUUGGAUAAUCAUGACAUUGGAAUAAAGUGGGAAGGAAAAAUUCCAUCAGCACAAAAUAGGGAAGUAAUCCCAACUUGUAGUCACAGUUUUCUGACUGGCUUUGUUUUAAAAGAGGAUGGCAGUCCUUGUUCGUGUCAGUGUGCCACUGGGUUUUUGCUGUUCCGUGUAAUUCAUAUCAACUUUGUGUUGCCAUUUGCAAGGUAAAAGGCAAAGCUGUAGUGUAUUCACCUAUGUAGACAGAUUGCUAGAUAUCUUUUUGAUCUGGGGCGAGUUCAAUAUUGAUUCCAGACUUAUUUGGAUUUUUUUAGUAUUAUUUUCCCCUCCCUUUCUAAUUUAAAUAGACAAAUUAAGCAAAAGUGUGUGUUCACAACCAAAUGUUGAUGCCCUUAUCUACUGAUAAUAUCCUCUCAAUGUUCACUGAGGCAUAGAAAUUAUUUCAGAGUAGAAAUUGCAGCAUGAGGAUAAACUCACCUCUUUGUUCUGAAAAUAGAACUUUAUCACUAUGCUUUCCGGUGGUUUUCCCUUUUACAAUCGAAAUCUUGUGCCUCCCAAGUGCAUUGGAAAAUGACAAAAGCCUGUCUCUCCAAAUUCCUAUUUAACAGUUUGAUUUUUUUUUUUUAAUCACCAUCUUUCAAAUCUUAGCUCAACUCUCACCAAGUGAAAAUUGGCUACUUGGGAGAAAGUUAACUUUCUAUGGUGGGAUGGUGAAGGAUGAGGGACAGUUUACAUAGGAAAAGAAAAAAAAAAGUCUAAAGUCCAUGUUGAAAAACCACACUACCACUUAUUUUCUGCUAACCCUAAAUUAUUUUUGCGUAUACGCUUGAGGUUAUAGUCUGUGCCUAGACCUAAAAUGCACCAGCGGGGGGGAUUUUAAAAAAUCCUUCAAAAUACCAGUUUUUUCCCAACAAGUACAAUUGUUCUUGUGCCUUCUGUGGCUUUCGAUUUCAUCUUUUUGACUUUAUUUCCAAUUACUACAGCUGCAAUAAACACUAGAUUUUUUUUCUGGCUGUUUGACAUAACGUUGAUAGCUAUGCAUAUUUUGUGUCUUUUUAAAACAAAGCGGGAGAAUACGUUUUUGAAGAAGAGAAUUUUUAGAACAGUUUGAUACCGCAAAUUAUUUUUUCCUCAAUUGUUUGAGCAGCAUUCGAGUUUUGAAAAUUCUUGUAGAAGCCAAUUUUUUGUAACUGUGGUGCAAAUCUUGUGUUUUCUUAGCCUAAUGAAAAGUAGUAUAGAAGCAAUAUUUCAUACCAUGUGCUAUAUAUGUGUGCGCAGAUGUGUGAACAUAAAAUCACAUACACACAUAUACACACAUGUAAAAAUAUACAUAUAUAUAUAUGCGUGUGAAGUGGAAAGCUUACCUUUUCCUAUCUAGAUUUAAGAACCUAUUUUAGACAUUUGUUAUGUUUUGUGAAAAGAAUGUUCUAUUUGCAACAAAACAUUUAAUUCUUACUGUAUCUCUGGCUGUUUAAUGAGGACGUUUCACAUUAAAUGGUAAAACACAUGGAAGAUGUUAGAAUGUAGUAAUUAUUUAAGUAAACGUUCACCCACAUAUUCCUGAAGUUUGCUUUGUGCCUCCGAGUAUUAUUUAAUUAAAGAAGUGUUUUAUGUUUGCAGAAUCUUUGUCACUGUACUAGGGAUGUGGGUGAAUAUCAUUUAAAAAAAUUUAAAACAACAAAAAAAAAGCAAAACAGAAACACUAAAGCAAGAGGGGAACUUUUAUAAAGCAAUGUAAAUAUUUAACCUCAUGGCUGUCAUUAUGUAAGACAUGAGAUUUUAAUAAAUAACUACAUUCUCACGACAUCUGUUGAAUUUACUAGGAACACUACAGUGACUGUAUAGACAGUUGAAAGCAUUCUUGAAAAUCCUGCUCUCUCCUUUUAAAAGUUAACAAUCUCUUUUAUCAGAUGUCAAGGGCAAGGGUAAUGCAGUUUCUGUAAAUUUAUGAAAUUUCUUUUUCUAUGUACAUGAAGACAUUUAGUAAGUAACACCCCCCCUUCCCAUGCGCACAUGUGCGCAUACACACACACACACACACACACACACACACAAACACACACACUGUCAUAAAGCUAAUGAUUUGGGGACUUUAAAAAAUAGGAUGUCCUCCAGGAACAAUCAUAAAUUUAUGAAAGAAAGAGUAGUUUACAGACUCCCCUGAAAGAAGCAGUGUAUAUGUGAAGACAGUGCAAAAAUCUCUUUGCCAUGUAUAUUAUAGCGUAUUCAUUGGUGUGAAUAGUACAAAUGUUUCCUUCUGGUACAAACUCUGUGUUUGCAAAUUUACAAGAAGCAUUGUUUUCAAAAAGCUCCCCUUAAAAAAUGUAACUGGUUUAUAUGAGUAAGCAGUUACCGUAUUGCACUUAAAUGUUAUGUUGAAGGAAAUGCAGUUUUGUUUUCUGUAGAUCUGUUGGUUGUAAACCAUCUAUAAAACUAAAGCUAAAAUGCUCAUAUUCAGAGCUGGGAUCAAAACUGGUAUUUAACCUUUGCAUCUUCUUAUAAUUAUCCUUCUAAGAAUAUAACAGAAUGUGGAAGUGUCUGGACUUUGAGUCUUUUCAACUGAGCCUUCUCUCAAAUCUGACACCCCCUCAGAAUGCACAAACAUAAGCAGAAAAGGCAAACAAGCUUACCUUCUUUUGUGAAAACGUAUUCAUUCUGUAUUUUUUUAAAUAUUCAAUUCCCCUAAAAAUGGGGAGAAAAUAUUUUAAAAUUGUAUAUUACGACUUCAAAUUUAGAACUAAGAAAAAAAUGUAUUUGGGAUUGGUCUCAGCGCUACCUAGAAGAAUCAAAGGUCAUGGCUUCCCUCAAUAUUGUCCCAGCCAUUUCUCAUAUGUAUAUAGUAUAAACCGUGACAAAACACUGCCUUUAUAUUAUUUAGCAAUAUGUUGUAAAUAGCAUUAUUAAGCUCUUUUUUGUAAUAAAGACCCUUUGAUUUGAAUAUAGUACAAUAACUGAACUGAUAAAGUCAAUUUUUGAUUUUUGUUUGUUUUUUUUAGCUAGAGGCAAUUUCAAUUGUGAAUUUUUGUUGUUGUCUAUUGUUCUGAAGACUUUGCAUAAUUUAUUGGUUUAAUUUAUCCUAAUUUAUUUGAUGAAGGUGUACAAUUUUGUAUUACCAAGGAUGUACUGUAAUAUUAAUUGAUAUGAUAAACACAAUGAGACUCCCUGUCCAUAUUAAAAAGAAAAUAAAAAGGUGCAGUAGACAAUUGAUUUUAAAGGAAAAGUUAAAAAAAUUAGUUUGGCAGCUACUAAAUUUUAAAACAGGAAAAAAAAAAGUUGUUGUGGGGAGGGUGGGAAAGGGGUUUUACUUUGUGUGUUUUAAGCUUUUGUAUACUCUCCAAACUUUUACCUUUUGCUUUGUACCACUUAAAGGAUACAGUAGUCCAAUUGCCUUGUGUGCCUUCCAUCUCCUCUUAAACUGAAUGUAUGUGCAGUAUAUAUGCAAGCUUGUGCAAAAUAAAAUAUACAUUACAAGCUCA